CUCGGUUCCCAGUGUUCUGGCAGGUAAGGAACGCCGGCUCUUCGCCUCUCAGCGCGGCUUGUCCUUUGUUCCGGACGCCCGCUCCUCAGCCCUGCGGCUCCUGGGGUCGCUGCUGCAUCCCGCACGCCUCCACCGGCUGCAGACCCAUGGCCGAGCGCGGGGAACUCGACUUGACCGGCGCCAAACAGAACACAGGAGUGUGGCUAGUCAAGGUUCCUAAAUAUUUGUCACAGCAAUGGGCUAAAGCCUCUGGAAGAGGUGAAGUUGGGAAACUGCGGAUUGCCAAGACUCAAGGAAGGACUGAGGUGUCAUUUACUUUGAAUGAGGAUCUUGCAAAUAUUCAUGAUAUUGGUGGAAAACCAGCUUCAGUCAGUGCUCCUAGAGAACAUCCAUUUGUCUUGCAAAGUGUUGGAGGACAGACAUUAACAGUAUUUACUGAGAGCUCAUCAGGGGGAUCCAGAAUGACUGCUGGAGUUACUACUGUCAUAUCUACCUCUCAGGCAUCAAAAGGGAAGCAAGACGGGGAAGAUAAGCUGUCAUUGGAAGGAAUAGUGGUACAAAGAGCUGAAUGCCGACCAGCUGCCAGUGAAAACUACAUGCGAUUAAAAAGAUUGCAAAUAGAAGAGUCUUCCAAACCAGUGAGGCUAUCACAACAGCUGGACAAAGUUGUAACAACCAAUUACAAACCUGUUGCUAAUCAUCAAUACAAUAUCGAAUAUGAAAGGAAAAAGAAAGAAGACGGAAAGCGAGCUCGAGCUGAUAAACAACAUGUUUUAGACAUGCUAUUUUCAGCCUUUGAGAAACAUCAAUACUAUAAUCUUAAGGACUUGGUGGACAUCACAAAGCAACCUGUGGUGUACCUGAAGGAAAUCUUAAAAGAAAUUGGUGUUCAGAAUGUAAAAGGGAUCCACAAAAACACAUGGGAGCUGAAGCCAGAGUACAGACACUAUCAAGGAGAAGAAAAGAGUGACUAAGAAGACUCCUAGCCAGCAUGCUAGUGAAACGACUAGCAGCGAUGCUAUGCAAAAGGCGCUGAUACUGGAAGGCUUGAACACCGUAUGUUAAUAGGGGUUAAGUGACAGUACUUUGAUUUCUCUCGGUAAAUUUUUUAAACCUGUAAUUCUUGUAAAGUUUCUUAACUGUUUUUUUGAGGAGAAAGAACAGAUUUAUUUAUAGACUUAACUUGUAUUAAACCAGAUUAUUCACAGUAGGAAUAGGGGUUGGAGGAUUAAGAGGGUUUUUCUUAAAUAUUAGCUUUUAAUGUGUACAAUUAGGAAAUUUUUUUAAGUGAGGACUCUCUACCCUUGCCGUAUCUAAGGAGCUGAGGUAAUACAGAUCCAAGGAGAAUUGUAUAGCAAGAAAAAAACAGUCAACUACAGAAACUCUUAAAAGGAAUAAAAACCCAAAGUUCCUUAUUUUGAAAUUGUCAAAGAACAAAGCGGUGUUUUUCUUUUAAACAGGUGAUCACGUUUCGUGUUCAUACUCAACGUUAAUAAAAGGAGAGAGUUUGUAGUGAAAUGGCAGUGUUCAUCAUUGGCUUAUUUUACCGUAGUGAUGCUGAGAUGAGAAAUGUGCAGGAUCAUGGUCAGUUGAUGUUUCUUUUAUUUGCUUUUAAGAUAAUUAGAAAUUAAAUAUCUUUCCAAAAUUUGAAGAUAUGUCUCCCCCAGUCAGAUUAUAAGCUUCUCAAAACUGGCUUGCCCCCAGAAUUUUACUGCUUACCCAGCAGACAUGUAUUGACCAUCACAUGGCAAAUGAUAUCAGCAAAUCAAAAGAUGGGCGUAGGGGUCCAGCCGAGACAGAAAACGUUAGUUUCAAUUCCUGGGGCAUUAAAAUGUUGCUUUUCUCUUUCUCUUUAAUUAAUUUUUAAAUGAAAACAAUACAUGUAUAUGUUAGUUUUUUCUAGCACAACACAAUAUUAUAUAUUAAGCGAUCCAAAAUCAUACUGUCAAGACCAUCAAACAAAACAAAGAAGCUUAAGUGAACUAAGCACAGGGAAAAGUUGUUUUUUCACUCGUUCAUUUUGUCAUCUGCUUCUAGAUGCUGCAAUCAAGAAGUAGCAAAUGCCCAAGUUGCCAUAGUGUUUGCAGGAAAAAAAGAGAAAAAAUAAUAAAAAUAAGGAAGGAGCAAUGCCAAAAAUUGAAGAAAAUAUUAUAUAAUUAAAGCAAGAAGAUAUCUAUCCAUUGAGAAAAACAAUUUUUAUAUUAUUUGCUUUUAGCAGCAAAGCAUUAGAAUUCUGAGAUUGUUAUAGCACUAAGAAGAUUUUUAUUCUGUGUACACACUGAAAAAUAAAAUUCUGAGUAAAGAAA